AGCGCCCGCGCCCGCGCCCCAGGAAGUAGGGUUUGCCUUAGGUGAUUUGAAGUCUAAUAUCUUUCCCAAUGAGUUACACUCAUUUCCCAUCCAUCUAAUGGGCGCUGGCAGCGUGUUUCGAUUAUUCUUGGCUUCUGGCCUCCAUCCGACCAAAUAGCUGUUGCUACUCCUACAAGUUUUUCUGGUGCCCGUUAUCUCCACGACAGCCGAAUCCAAAGCUUUAAGAGCUGCUCGGCAGCUGGAACGAUCGGUGGCUUUUCCAACCCCGGGGGGGGGGCGGUGUGAAAGGUGACCCUCAUUUCGUUUGGAAGCGGUAACACUUCGGGGUCACAUCUCAGUCCAGUUCCUCCAGAAUAGGCGCUGCUGUCCGCCCCUUCCCUGCCCCACGAAAGAACAGGUAGCCCCAAUCUUGAGACACGCUCCUCCACCUUCGAAAUCUUCUCGGUCCCGGUUCCCCAGGACUCAGCCUUCACAGAGGCCAACUUCAGUGACUGUAUUUUUAAAUUCAUUGACACCCAAAUUCUAUGUGGCACUUACAGGGACCUCUUCAUUGAUAUCAGGACUAAUAUUUAUAUUUGAAUGGUGGUACUUCCAUAAGCAUGGCACAUCUUUUAUUGAGCAAGUAUCUGUAAGCCAUUUGCAACCACUGAUGGGAGGAACAGAGAGCAGCAUUUCAGAACCAGGUUCUCCUUCGAGGAACAGAGAAAAUGAAACCAGCAGACAGAAUUUGUCAGAAUGUAAGGUAUGGAGAAACCCUCUAAAUCUUUUCAGAGGAGCAGAAUAUAGGAGAUACACUUGGGUGACUGGUAAAGAGCCACUUACAUACUAUGACAUGAACCUGUCAGCUCAGGACCAUCAGACCUUUUUCACCUGUGACACAGAUUUUUUACGUCCUUCAGACACAGUUAUGCAGAAGGCUUGGAGGGAAAGAAAUCCUCCAGCUCGAAUCAAAGCAGCCUAUCAAGCUUUAGAAUUAAACAAUGACUGUGCCACUGCAUAUGUUCUACUGGCUGAGGAAGAAGCAACAACUAUUGUAGAUGCUGAAAGGUUAUUUAAACAGGCACUCAAGGCAGGAGAAACAAUUUAUAGGCAGUCACAGCAGUGCCAGCACCAAAGUCCUCAGCAUGAAGCUCAACUGAGGAGAGAUACCAAUGUACUGGUAUAUAUUAAAAGAAGAUUGGCAAUGUGUGCAAGAAAAUUAGGAAGAAUAAGAGAAGCAGUAAAAAUAAUGAGAGAUUUGAUGAAAGAAUUUCCUCCUCUUACCAUGUUGAACAUCCAUGAAAAUCUCUUAGAAUCACUUUUAGAAUUACAGGCCUAUCCAGAUGUUCAGGCAGUCCUAGCAAAAUAUGAUGAUAUAAGCCUUCCAAAGUCAGCAGCAAUCUGUUACACAGCAGCACUGUUGAAGACAAGGACUGUUUCAGAAAAAUUCUCUCCAGAAACAGCCUCCAGAAGAGGAUUAAGCACAGCAGAAAUUAAUGCCGUGGAAGCAAUUCAUAGAGCUGUGGAAUUUAAUCCUCAUGUUCCAAAAUAUUUAUUAGAGAUGAAAAGUUUAAUUUUACCUCCAGAACACAUUCUGAAACGGGGUGAUAGUGAAGCAAUUGCCUAUGCUUUCUUUCAUCUUCAGCACUGGAAACGAAUAGAAGGUGCUCUUAAUCUGUUACAGUGUACAUGGGAAGGCACCUUUCAUCAUGUUUCUGUUUACCCAAAAAAGGAGCUUCCUUUGUUCAUCCAUUUCACAGCAGGAUUUUGCUCUUCUACAGCAAUGAUAGCCAUUCUCACUCACCAGUUUCCUGAAAUCAUGGGUAUUUUUGCUAAAGCUGUGCUGGGACUCUGGUGCCCCCAACCCUGGGCAUCCUCAGGCUUUGAGGAGAAUACACAGGAUUUGAAGUCAGAAGACCUAGGUUUGAGUUCUGGCUGAGCCACGCACUGUUCAUGUGACCUUGGACAAAUCACCAAAUUUUUCUGAACAGCAUCUGUAAAGUGACAGUAACCCCUACCUCACAGGGUUGUUGUGAGGAUUACAUAUAUGCUAAAGCAUUUUGCAUAUGAAAAAGCUUCUUAUGAAUAUUGUUAUUCCUAGGCAAACCCCCCUUGGAAGCUGUCAAAAAGGACAACUGUAGAUGAAAUUGUCUUCCUUUUUUCUUCAUUCAGCUUAGCCUUUCUGUUUGGCCAGGGCUACUUACAGGGGCUGUUGGGGUUGAAGUCAAGUCACCGCAUUUUGGCUCCUUUGGUCAAAGAGAAAGAACUCUAAUGUCCAGCUGCUCCAUCGAUAUACUCAUAGAAUGGAAGUGAGCAAAGGAAAAUUUUAAGCCAGGAUAGUUAACCGUUAGGGGGCCAGUGGGAGAAUGCUUGCCUUGCAUUUGCACAUCCAGAAUGACUAAAACAUCUUAAGUAAAUGAGGAAUAGCCACCGAGAUGCUCAGAGAUAAUAUAAGCCAUGAGUGGGAAGUGGGAAAAUGAGUUUGUCAACGCCCUCUCUUUUCUAUCCCUUUACCUUUGAGGUCAGGGACAGGGCAUAUUACUGACACCCCACUGGCUAUUGCCCUAUACCUGCCAAUCACCCAAAGAAAAUAAUAGCUUCUGAGAAAGCUCAAUUCACUGUAGCAACUGUGAUAUAUUUACCCUAAUAAAGCCACCACUUGGUCUUUUCCAGUGCUUCUCUCUUAUGGAGAUCAUCCCUGGAAUCCAAAGCUCUCCAGUUUUCUAACCCAGUUAAGAGUUAAAAACAACCACAGGUCAUGAGCAGUAGGCUUGGCAGUUAUACCCCAUGCAGUCAUAGGAGACUGCUCCAUCAUUCUCAGCACAUAGGGUGCACAUCUCACUAUCUCUGGCAUGAACCAGCCUUGCGAACUUAUACAGUCUCAGCCACUCUGCUUUGAUGGUAAUUCUUCACCACUGAUCUCUCCUCACCAUGCCCUUCCUGCAUCCUUCCCCCAACCACCCACCAGAGGAGUUCUGGUCCCCAAACCAAAGAGUUGCCUGCAGGUUGGUAAUGUGACUUUGUAGAUAUUCCUUGAUUAAAGCCAGACCCUAUUGGUAUCCUUUUUGAAGUACUGGAUCGAAAUCUAAUUGCUUUUUUUUUUAAUUGUUGGGGAGAGGAGGAUGAGCAGAACUCCUAUGCAGCCUGAGAGAAGUUCUCUAUGUGUCUGUAUAUGUACACCUCUGUGUGUGUGUGUGUAACCUCAUGGUUGUGCUCAGGCUGACAGGGAGGGCAAAGAGUGAAAAGGAAGCAUCUCUUUCUUGUUAUCCAACAUUGCUUCAAAGAUGCCCAACCCCCGUAGUAGCAGGCAGUUCCCAAGUGGAGGGUCGGGGCAGAGGCCUCCACCAAGGCCAUCAAUAACCAGGUGUGAGCUACAGGUCUCUGUGUAAUGUGAAGCUCUCCCGUAUUUCAUUUCUGCACCCAGGGGGCGGCUCUGCAGGAUUGCUUACGGAGAACUCUGUGUCUGGCACCUCUCUCCACAAGGCCCAGGCGCCCAGGGUCCCACCGACCUGCCCAGGAAUGCAUCACAUUGUUCUCUGGUGCUGUAAUUUGGCUGCAGGAGCUAGGCUGAAUGCCUCCCAGGGAUGAGAAACAUACUCUCCCUGGCGUCCUCCCUUCGCCCCAGCUAGCUUGAGCUUCUGCCCUAUGACCACUGAGUGCAUUUAAAUAAAAACCUCAGAAAGACUGAGGAAAAAAAAAUCCUAAUUAUCUCUCUUCUGUUAAGCCAUGUAGAGACUCGUGUCCUGAGUGGGUCUGAGAAUUUGGCAAAGACUUACUGGUUGGUGUUCUUGAUAAGGGAAGUGAGACAAAGGAGAAGAAAUUACUCCCUGCAACAGGAGGAAUAGAAAUGAAGCAGUGAGUGUUCAGAAAUUAGAUCUACAAGAAGUUUUGCAAACAGACCCUCAGGGCCAGGCAAUGUUUGUUUUUGUUUUUUGUUUUUUGUUUUUUUUUUUAAUCUGAAGCCCCUGAUUUUAUUUUUCCAGCAUCACUCUAAGGAAGAGUGUGGAUUAGUGCCAUUAUUCAGGGCUGGUAUUAAUAAAAGUUAGCUUUUAUCUGCAGGGCUAGGUUAAGGCUGGCAUUCUUACUUUUACAUUAAAAAAACUGGCUACAGGCUGCGCAGCUGAGGUACUUCAGUCAUGUGCCUUCUCUAAAGGAUUCUUAGAUCCUUAAAAUAUAUAGUAUGUUUUAAGUUUGUAUCUAAAUAGCACUUACUGUAAUGUAUUAUACCUAAAUGUUUAUUAAAAGUUAGAAGAAAUGAGUACCAACAGGAAGGAAUGGAAGAGAGGAGAGGGGCUAAGACAUUGCUGAUCUGAGGGACAGACCUCUAUCAAAUAGAAGAGGGCUGGGAGAAGGGGUGAUUAGAAGCAGAGUGAGGGAACUAAAUGGAGCCCUGACUGCACCAAAUAAAGUUCUCAUUUUGCUGCUUGUUCCAAAUAAA